GCAGAUCAGAAAGAAGGGGUUCCUGGUCAUACACCAGUACUACCAAGGACAGCUUUUUUCCUGCAAGGUAAAUGUUCUUCAUGUGUUUUUGUUGGUUUUAAGCGCUUGUGAUGCACUUCGGCACUGUUUCUGUGGAUUGUGGGUUUUGCCUUCAGGGGACCAGAGAUCUGAGCAUGUCACCUGAGACCUCUGUGAUUCCUGCCACUGUCUAACUGGCCAGGACAUCUGCCGCCACCUCGCGUGGCCAUCCAAGAUGGAGCACCUCGGCUCUCUGGGCUGGGUUCUUCUCAACUUAUCUGCAGUUAUCACCCCUGCCCAAAAUUAAGGUUUCUUUUUCCUUUUAAAACCAAACCAUGUUCUGGUUUAUUUCUAUUGCUCUAUUUCACGGAGGCUAUUUACUGUGAUUUUAUCUUCUUUAAAAUGUUUUCAGGAAAAGCGCGUAUUGAUAAUUUAGAUUGUAUGGCUUAUUGGCCCAAUGGGGGUAGUUUAAUUUUAGUUCCUGCGGUUCUGUUUUUCUAAAAAACUUCUUUACAGUACUUUAGUGGAUAAAUUAUCUAGAGUCAUAUGUUACUGAAUGUGAUACUGGUUAUUUGAGUGAUUUUUGGCGCCAAGGGUUUUUAAUGGGUGUGCUUUAUAACCACAUGGAAUUAGAGGUUUUCUCUUUUCCAUUUGUUCUCUAAAAAUAAAAGCAAUUUGUAUAAUGCUUAAUUGUAGUGUUUUUGUAGGAUUGUCUGAAUUAUUUGUUAUGCUUAUGACCAUAUCAAUGAAUAUUCACUCAAAUUCUGGGAGAAAGGCUUUUAUCUACAAUAGAAAUUUUUACACAGUUGAUAUGGGAUAUUUAUUUCAGAAACUGCCCAAACAUAGACACUUUGGAUUUUGUAGUAUAAGCUUUUACUUAAUUACCACUAUCACAUAACACUAAGAACCAUUGACAAAUGAUAACUAUAAAAGCCAUUCAGACUGGAAAUGCGAACAUUAAUCAGGAUGUUUAUCAAAACCGAACUUUUCUUUUACACAGCAACUUGUUUUCUAAAAUUACUCUGUCAGAACUAUCAGUAAGCAAAUAAAGGUGGCUUAUCCACACACAUCUUGAUUUUGAAUUUACAUACAUUUGUCAUAAGUUUGGUUUCUAUUAAGUAUAAUUGUUUAAAGAAUGUCUGUGUAGACAAAUUUGAAUAGAAUUAAUCAUUUACCUAUAAAUGUGAAUUUCUGGAAACUGCAAAAUGUGACCACCAAUGUUACUUUGCACAUCUCACCUGAAUAGUUUCAAACAAGCAAAAAUGUGAAACUGAGAUAAGAGGGACUUGAACCCCGUAAAAGAACAGACUAAAAAUAUGUUGUGUCUUAUUUUAAGUAAAACUAUUAAUGAGAAUAAAAUAAAUUCGAAUGUGAAGGAAUGUCAGUAUUUUUCUUAUAUUUACGAAGGAAUAAAAAAGAACUAUGCGAAAGUUAAUUCAAAAUAUAAAGGUCCCCUGUUUAAAGUUAAGUUUACAUUGCUAAAGCAUCAACCCCAUAUGUUACAAAGAUAUUCCUCUUCAUUCUAGCUCACCCCCAGGAACAUCAGGGGAAAAAUCUUCUAGGUCUUGCCCUUUGAACAAGCACUGCUGUGGUGGGAUGGAGUUGUGCCUAGGAGGACAUUUCCUUAGCAAUCCCAGAGACCCUUUUCUUUGUAGCAUUUAAAUUUUUGUCUCUUUUGUAAAUUAUGCCUUGAAACAAUUGGUAAUUUGGGAAACAAUUUCAGUGCUUUAACUUCAUUUAUAAUUCUAUCUCUGAACCCUUUGGGGAAGGGAAGACCAACAAGUAAAGUCUCAUUUACUUGUUGUUAAAGUACCAUUUAACUUGGAGAGGACAGGAAAUUAAUAAUAGCACUCAAUAAUUAUGAGCACGUAGUGUAAGCAGCUACUCUUUAUGCAUUACCUCGUUUAAUCCUCUCAGCUACCUUUAGAGAUAAGGAAUGGGCUAGAUAAUUGAAGGAACCGGCCAUAGGUCACUGGGCAGUUGGGGUGGGGGGCAGUAGAUGGCCAGGAUUUCAGGCUCCUACUGACUGUGUGUGUUACAGAUCCUCCCUUCCAGGCCAGCAUAUUUUUCUCAGAGGUAGGUGAUUAUAGACUUUUAUUACUGAAGCUAGCUAACAAGAUCUUGGCACUCACAGUUUUAAGAGAGAAUAAAAGAGAGAGAGCAAGAGAAAGAAGAGAGAGAGAGAGAGAAGAAAAACUUUGUAAUAAAUUUACAAACAUUUUUAUUUUUAUAAAUAAGAGAUACCAUUGCAGGUUUUAUAUAAUAAUGGGCUGAAGAACUAUUUUUAAAUUAAUGCAUAAUUUUACUAAAGAAUUGUGUGCCUUUACAAACUUGCCUCGACCCACUUCCCCAAUCUUAUUUCUUGUCACUUCCUUCUGUUCAACCUCCCACUACCCCAUCCCCUCCCCCGCCACUGCUAACCCACAUUUUGGUGCACCAGACCACAAGCCACCAGAAAGUUCCAUUCUCUUUCACCUUUUUUCACUGCAACUGUUUCUUUAAUUGCAUUCUUCUUUAUUUUUAAAACUUCUGAUCAUUUUUCAAGGCGGACUUCAAGAAACAUACCCUUUUGGAGGCCUUCCCAUCUUCUCCCUGCCCCCACUAAAUGUUUCUUUGGUGUGCAUUUGCUCAAUGCUUUGAUCUUGGAGUAAGUAUAACAUUAAUCACAUUGUCUUAGUUUCAAGUACUUAUUUGCUGACAGACCUGAGCUCCUUCUCCAUCUUUCCUGGCACAUGUAGAUACUAAAGGCAUUUAUUGAAUUGAAAAUUUGUCACAAGUAUUUUUUUUCUCAGCUUCUUACAUACGCAUGAAAGACUUUGAUUGUACUUAUUAACUUAAUAUUUACUGAGUUUCCAUUUAUUGCUAUGAAUGAAGAUGCAACAAUAAUAUAAUAUUUUGCAUUCUACCAUGUUUCAGCUUUACCGAAGCCCUAGUCUCAUUUUAGCUUCAAAGUAUCAUAUAGACAUUGACCUCAAGAAAUUUAAAAAAUUGUACAAUGACUAACAAACAGGGAAAAUUACAAUCUCAUUUUUUUAGUAUAAAUACAUUGGUUGGGCCAAAACUUAGCUACCCUUGCCAAAACUAUAUACCCAAUAAUGGGCCUCUUUGAUGACAAAGAACACAAGGGCAGUUGUUAACUUUUACUUAGUCACUUUGGAUUAUUCUCAGAAAAUUCUCAAGUCAACUUCUCCUUGUUACCUAAAGAGUACAGGCCCUUCUGUGUAUACAGGAGAGAUGGCAAGCAACUUUUAAAAUCAGCUUAGGUAAAAUAAAAUUAAGAAAUCUGCUUAUAAGGUUAUACUUAUGAAGAGUCAAACACUUAUAAAAUAAGAUUAUAAAGGCUUGGACUUUAUUACUAAUAGUAGAUUUUAUAGUAGAGUGACAUUAUUUCAGUUAAUCUAAUUUUCUUCCUAGUGUUUUUUUAUCUGCUAGUUUCCCAACUUACAGAUAUCAAAUGAAAUGAUACUAUUUCAUCUGUAUACUGAACACUGCAGAAAUAAACAUUAGAAUUAGGACACAUCAAAAUAUAAAACUAAUCAGUGUCCACAGAUUUGAAGAGUUUCAAGUGUUCCUAUUUUGCCAGAUGGAAGCGCACUCCUUAAAAAAGUGUUAAUGUUCUACAGGGUCUUCAUUUUGAGGCUCUCGGAAGUCACCUCCUGAUUAGAUGUUGGUUUCCUAGGGAUAUCUCCCUAUAGCUGCUGUGGCCGUGGUGUUCCCCAGAUGGCAUCUCCUUGUUGCUUUCCUCAGUUCCCUUCUGAUCCAACUUCCUGCCUUAUACUAUUGACUGUUCCUGUUGUUUUGGUUUGUCAGUUUCAAUGCUUACAUCAGUCUGCCCAGAAAUUGCAUAACUGCUCCAUCUUGUAAGAUAUCGGUGGGGGAUGGGGGGGAGUGGAAGGCGCUUCAAUUAAUCAUCCUAAUAAUAACGUUAAUACUUACAUUGAAUCAGGUGUUUUUCUAAGUGCUUUAACCCUAUGAAAGCAUUUAGUUGUCAUACAGUCCUGUGAGGUAGUGUCUGGUGUCCUCUUCAUAUUUGAAGGCAAGUUCAUUCAUUCACGUAUUUUAUUUAAUUUUCUACAAUUGGAUCAAUUUUGUCUUAACUGUUGAAUUUCAAGGCAACUUCCUGGAAUAAACAGGUAGCAAACCAUGGUGCUUAUUUGUAACUAAGCCCUCAAGUUGAGCUCAAAUAAUCAUAAUACUUCCCCAAAUAAAUGCAUCUAUAUGAUAAGUGCUUUUAUAAACAAAUUAUUCUGUGUCAUCAUAUCAUCAUCAUCAUCAUUAUCAUCACCAUCAGCAGCAGCAGCAGCAGCAACAGCAUCAGUAGUCAGCCCCUCUGUACACUUGACUGAGUAGAAGUUGGUUGUUAACAAUUACAGGCCUCUGCAUGGGUCACAAAACAUGAUCUCCACCCUCAAAAACUUUAAAAGGUUCUUAGUCUUUUGUUUGUUUGUUUGUUUGUUUUUUGAGACAGAGUUUCACUCUGUCGCCCAGGCUGGAGUGCAGUGGCGCGAUCUCGGCUCACUGAAACCUCUGCCUCCUGGCUCACCCAGGCUGGAGUACAGUUGCGUGAUCUCGGCUUACUGAAACCUCCGCCUCCUGGGUUCAAGCGAUUCUCCUGCCUCAGCCUCCCGAGUAGCUGGGACUACAGGCGCCCACCACCACGCCCGGCUAAUUUUUUGUAUUUUUAGUAGAGACGGGUUUCACCUUGUUAGCCAGGACGGUCUCGAUCUCCUGACCUCGUGAUCUGCCUGCCUCGGCCUCCCAAAGUGCUGGGAUUACAGGCGUGAGCCACCGCGCCCGGCCUUUAAAGUUUAGAAUAAUUUUAGUCAAGUGGCAUUCACAUUUUCUAGUCUGUUGUGACUGAUAGACAUGAAUAGAUUAAACAUUCUACUUUUUAUACCCAAGUACACAUAUCUAUGAUUGUAUAGUAAUGGCCAAAUAUAAGUGUCCUAAAAACUGAGAAAGAAUGAAACAUUGCUUUAAAUGUUAGUGGAAGAAGAGAGGUAAAAGUGAACCACUUACUGGGUUUAAGUAAGUUUUGCUCAACUUCAGAGCCAUGGCUGUGUCAGCCCCACUUGCAAGUACAAGGAGCCUGUUACUCAAAGAUGGUCAGUUGUUCUUUCUGGCGGAAGGAAAAGCUAUGUUAAAUUGGGGAACUAGCAAACCCACAGUUCUGUGGUUGCAGCAUUGAUUCUUAUUUCAGCAUCUGUUACAUGGACAGAAGGGAGGGUCUCCCUCCCUCUCUCUCUCUCGCUCUCUCACACACACACACACACACACACACACAAAUAAACACACAUACACGGAAACACACACACACACUCACUCACACACUCCUUCUUGACUGGAUAAGCUAAAGUGAAAAAGAGAUUAUGUUUUCCAUAGCAGAAAAGCUGACACCAAAUUCAGCAAGCAGAUUAAUUAUGCAUGUGAAUUGCAAUCUCCCAGAUAAUUUGCUUUCCUUCUUUUUCUGGUUGCACUUUCUAGAGGGAAGUGAAUUAAUGGAACAAUUACCUUGUAUUUAAAUAAUACCCUGCAUUUUGUUUCCUCAGUCUGGUAGUAGUCACUAAAAUUUAUCCAAGCUAUGUAUCCAAAUGUGUGAAGUAAAAGGAUACACAAAUGUUAUUUGUAUAAAAUUUGCAUAUUUUCCCUAUUCAGCAUUCCUUAGGCAAAGUUUAAAAUUAGAAGUGGAUCUUUAUUAACCUCAGGUGCAACUUUUUUUCCAUAAAAACCUUUUAUAAUAAUUCAUGAGAUUAUAAUAGAUGUGUGUGCAUUCAAUAUAGCUUCCAUCCUGAAAAUGUUUUUUCAGUUUUUAUUUAUUUUUAAAUUGACAUAUAACGGUAUGUAUUUAUGGGGUACCUAGUAAUGUUUCAAUACAUACAAUGUCUAGUGAUGAGAUCAGGGUAAUCAGCAUAUCCAUCAUCUCAAACAUUUUUUAUUUCUUGUGCUGGAAACAUUCAAUCGCCUCUCUUCUAGCCAUUUUAAAACUAUGUACUGUUAACUAUAGUUAUCCUAUAGUGCUAUAGAACAUGAGAGCUUAUUCCUCCUGUCUAGCUAUAAUUUUGUAUCUAAACAAAUCUCUCCUAUCCUCCACCUUCCCCCUACCCUUCCCAGCCUCUAGUAAUCUCAGGUGUAACAUUUAAAAAGUAGAUCCUUUGUACCUCCUUGACAUCAUCUGCUCAUAUCACCCUCACCAGAAAGGCCAGCUUGAACAAAGAAGAGUGGGAUAUAAAUUCUUUAUAGAGAAAGCUAGGUAAUAGGUGCAAAGUGGGAGUAAGGAAAAAAGAGAAGAUCAUGCCUGUAGUUUUGCACUGUUGAGCACUCUUUUGUCAUCUUAAAAAUGCGAACUGAACUUCCCCCACUGUUUCUAAUGCUUUAUAAACAGUUUUAAAGUUUCCCUUUGAAAAUAUGGAAUAUGGUAGGCACCUUGGAAAACUUUGGAUUUUUUCCUUUUCUUGCUGUCAUUCAUGUUGGGACUGUUCCUCAAAAUAUCAUGGAUUCUGUUUCUUUUCUGUGACCACUGAGAAUGACAGUUGUGAUACUUCAUCUACCUGGUGAUGUUCACACAGUUUUUCUCCUCCCUCCGUACCCACCCUACUGUUCACUGCACGCAGUUCUUCCUCCAGUACCAUAUCUCCAGUACCAGUUCUUUAAAGCUGAGUGUCUGCAGCUCCCAGGCACAAAAGAGGCAAAUGUGGUAUAAAGAAAGGGGAGCAAAGGUAGAGACAGAUUUGGAUUUAUAUUCUGGGCUCUUGGUAAAUGUGGAGGCUGAGCAAGUCUCUGGAGCCUCUGAAGUUCAGUUUCCUCAUCUAUAAAAUCAGGCAAGUGCUAUCUACUCGCUAGGUGUGAUGUGGGUUAUUUUCCCCUUCCAUUUUCCCAUGUUGUCGUCUAGGUAGAUAUGGAGCAUAUCUACUCCACCCAGCGUCACCACUGACUUACUGAGCCCCUAAUAUUUACUAGGCAUCAUGCCAAACGCUUGAAAGAUAAUUACUCUUUUAUUUUCAUACAUAGCUAGGUAAAGUUGUUAUUAAUUAUAUCCUUAUUCCAGAUGACCAAGCUGAGGUUCAGGGAGGGUUAAGUGACUUGUCUGGGGUCACAGAACCAGUAACUGGCAGAGUCAAGAUUCACACCUUUCCUCUCUCUCAUUUUAUGUUGGCAGUUUCUUAAAAGUAUAAUCCAUGUCUAUUUAAACUGUUUUGUAUCUUCUAACAUGAUCCACUAGUUGCUUCCUGAUAAUAUGUCUAUAUACUUUUUUGUGUUUCCAUGAUUAUUGAAUGAUUAUUUGUAAUUCCACAUUUUCUUUCUUUUUUCUUUUUUUUUUUUUUUUUGAAGAUGGAGUUUUCGCUCUUGUUGCCCAGGCACAAUCUUAGCUCACUGCAACUUCCGCCUACUGGGUUCAAGAGAUUCUCCUGCCUCAGCCUCCUGAGUAGCUGGGAUUACAGGCACACACCACCACGCUCAGCUAAUGUUUUUGUAUUUUUAGUAGAGACAGGGUUUCACCACAUUGGCCAGGCUGGUCUUGAACUCCUGACCUCAGGCGAUCCCCCUACUUCGGCCUCCCAAAGUUCUGGGAUUACAAGUGUGAGUCACUGCACCCGGCCUAUAAUUCCACAUGUUCUAUCAGGAAGAGAUCCCAAGUCUCCUUUUGUUAGGUCGGCUGGUAUACCAAACAUAUUUGAGAAAUAAAUAUAAAUGCUUGAGGAUUUUAUGGUGGGAAGUCUUUAAAAUAAUAGCUGUGAAGAUAUUAGAUUAGGCUAUUUAGGCACUUAAAAUUUUGAUAAAAGAAAUGUUAUACAUAUUCCAUUGUACGUUGGUAUUGGUAAAUAUUUACCAACUAAACUGUAACUUUUAAAAAAAAUGAAGAUAAAGAGAGCCCAUCAAAUUAAUACAAAUUUCCUGUCUCAAUUUAUCUGUAACUUCUCCUUUUGUUUUUUUCUGCAAAUAAGCUUGUCAUUAGAGAUUCUAAAAUCCAAGAAGCCUAUUGAGAAUGAGAUCACAUUAUUACAAAUAAAUAGAAGUUUCUGUUAUCAUUGCUUGUAUACAAAUGUCUGCUGUACAUUGUCUCACUGUUUUUCAGCUCAGACUACAAUGGUAAAAAUGCCUGGAGAAUUAGAGAGUGGAGAGGAGGUAGAGUGUAGUGCAGGAUAACAGAAUCAGUUCUGAGCAUUGGUGCAUCUGACAGAGAGGAGAUGUUGCCCAGUGGUCCUCAUCACAGAUGCCCAGAGAUCUCUUUUCUUUUCAUGGCUCAUAGUGUAUGUGGUUGGGCUUUUCUUAAGAUUGCUGUACAUUUUUCCACUCUGGCCAUACUUCCUCAACUGUUAGAAGGUACUUUCCACUGUCAGUACUCAGGCAAGGCAAAGCCCGGAGCCCCUUCACCACUCAGGAUGAGCUAAUACCAAUGCUGUUGGCUUUGGGUUGGUAUCAUGUACCAGUUCUGCAAUACCUGACUUCAAGGACUCCGAAUAAGAAAUGUGGUACCAAAGCCAAAAUAAGCCAGACUGAGAACAUUAAAACAUAGAGCAUGGAUGUGAGAUCUAGAUUUACACCCACACAAAACACAUAGUAUACAACACAACUAAUCUUUGCUUUUAAGUUGCGACUUGACAAUAUUUCCUACAGUUUAUACUAGAAAUUGGGAUUUGUUCUCCAAGAUAAUUUUGCAAAAGUUCUAGUUCUUUUACAUUUUCUUUUAACUUCCUCUGUUCCUUCCCUUUUCCUUCUUUCUUUCCUUCCUCUCUUCCUCUCUUUCUCCCUUCAGUCACCAGGCACUGUUGUAUAUAUUUUAAACACUCUGUCUCACCUAAUCCUAAUGCUGCCCUAUGAAAUGAACGGUGUGAUUGCAUUAUUAGCACCCCUUCUUUAAAGAUGAAGAAACUGAGGCUCGGAAAAUUUAAGUAACACAUUCAAAUACACACAGCAAAAAAUAGUUGAGUCAGAAAAUUCAGCAUUUCACCAUACCAUGUCACUGCCUAGUUGAUUCAUUUUAAAAACAAUAUAUAAUGAUCCUAAUUUCAUAAAGGAAGCGAGGAACAUUAGCUUUUGUUUGGAAUGCCUUUACAUGGGUGUAUCCCUGUAUCCUAGAUCCACACAUCUAAGAAGUAAAGCACAUUUCAUGGACCGUGCAUCUCAAAGGUUUUUUAAAUAAAACUUUAGGUUCUUAAAAUGCCAACUGACUUGUGUUUUUCCCACGCAUUGCUUCGACCAAACUAAGACUCCAGAGGUUCCACUUACUUCUCUUUUUGGACCAGUCACUGACUUACUUUGAGACUUUGGGGAGUGACUUCACCCUCCAGGGCCCCUAUUUCCCCAUUCUAACAUGUUCAGUUCCCUCCUGUCUUUGCAGUAUUUUCUAAAUGGGAGAUAAUGACAUAAGGAGAAAGCUAUGCACACACAAACCAAAAUGGUUUCCGGGCAGAAUUAUUUUGUUGUUUGUAUUCACAUUACCUGUGGUGAGUGGAGUAUAGCCUGCAUCACCGAGGUUUUGCCUCUAGAAACAAGAGCUAGUGAGAACGAGCAGCACGCUGACACCACCUCACCAACCUCUCAUCCUGGAGGUCUCCUCCUGCAUCCCUGUCUGUAGCCACACCCAACCUGCCACAGCUUCCUGUGUGUGCUUUUGCUUUGCACUUUGUAGAGCUAUUUUCUCUUUCUUUUCUUUUCUUUCUUCCUUUUUUUUAAUGUAAUGGAGCCUUGCUCUGUGGCCCAGACUGGAGUGCAAUGGCGUGAUCUCAGCUCACUGCAACCUCUGCCUCCCGGGUUCAAGUGAUUCUCCUGCCUCAGCCUCAUGAGUAGCUGGGAUUACAGGCACCCAUCACCAUGCCUGGCUAAUUUUUGUAUUUUUAGUAGAGAUGGGUUUUCACCAUGUUGGCCAGGCUGGUUUUGAACUCCUGACCUCAGGUGAUCCACCCAUCUCAGCCUCCCAAAGUACAGGGAUUACAGGCGUGAGCCACCAUGCCUCGCCCUGCAGAGCUAUUUUCUCUGCCUGAAAUGCCCUUUUCUAUUUUGUCUGUUUGGAAAACUACUGGUUCCCUAAGACUUAGCUCAGUGGGCAACAUCACCUUCUCUGGAAAACCUUCUUUUGCCUUCCCAGGCAGAGUUAAAUACAGUUGUUCCAUGGUAUCCACAGGGCACUGGUUCCAGUAACCCCCUCGGUACUAAAAUCCAUACAUACUCAAGUCCUGCAGUCAGCCCUGUGGUACCCACAUGUACGAAAAGUUGGCCCUUGGUCGCCCUGAGUUUCGCAUUCUGCGAAUACUUGUAUUUUCCAUCCACAUUUGGUUGCAGAUGCUGACCCUGAGGACAAUGAGGGCUGACUGUAUUGAAGAAAAUUGCGUAUAAUUGGACGCACACCAUUGAAACCUGUGUUGUUCAUAGGUCCACUGCACUUCAUUCUCUGUGCUCCUGUAGCUCCAUGCAAAUAAUAUCUUUAAAAUAUUCAUAUUAGUGUAGUCUUGCAUUUGCGUGACUAUUUUGUUUACUGGACUGUGUGCCCCUCAGGAGCAAGGAUUCUCUGCUGUUCAUCUUGGUAUCUUUAGUACUUAGGACAAGGUAUGUGCUUUAUUAAAUGUGAGUGAAUGACUGAGGUGUGGAGGCCACGGGCAAAGAGGACCCUUUUCUCCACCAGUGGCAGGGGGGACACAGGCAGAAAAGAUCAAGCCUGGUUGUGUUCUUGCUCUUCUUAAUACUUCCUUUAAAGAUGUUGAGAAACCGAAGACACAUUUAGAACUUCCCUAAAGAGCCUAGGAAGGGCCCAGUCCUAAGUAAAACCUUGCAGAAAUAUGUGUUUCCCUAAUUAACAUGAGGUCAGAGCUUUGACCUUCAAGGGCAACCCCAAAGGAUGGCAGGGAAACUCGAGAUACAGGAAUCCCAUAGCCAGAAAUGAUAGGAAAGGCAGGAGGCCACUCCAGUUUAUAGCUGUGCGACCCUGGGCCAGCUAUUUAAACCUCAGUUUCCUCAAAGUGGGAAUCAUAGUAAUACCCUAUAGGAUUGUGGUGAGAAUUAAAUGUGAAUGCAUGUAAAACAUUUAGCACUGAGUUAACCACUCAUUAAUGUUAACGGCUAUUAUUACUGACCAACUGGUCUUUUCAUUUGUUCUUUAGCUAUUUGCCCUUUCUCUGACUCCAAAUAGAUAGGCUUUCUAUAGAGAGAGCAUGGAGUCUCUGAUGAAUGAAGAAAAAAACAGACUGAUCUUUAAGCAAUCUCCUACUGCUCUGUUGAAAUCUAGGUCAAAUGUCACUUCCUCUAGGGGGCCGCCUUUGGCUCUCCAGGGGAGAGCUAUUUUUUCCCUCUUCCUGUGGAUCUAAAAAGUUUCGCUGUAUUCUAGUUACUGUGUCUCUCUCCCCUACUCAACAGGCCAAAGCCACGUCUGUGUGUUCUCAGCAUCUAACACAGGACCUGGCAUAUAGUAGGUGUUUGGCAGAUGUCUAUUGAAGGAAGAAAUUUACAAAUGUAUGAAUUUUUUUAGUGACAGACAUUUAGAAUUACUGGGGGAUGAAUAGCAUUGUUCAGAUAGUGAGACGCAAAUUACAUGCAGGUAAAUGCUAGCACCUAUAUUUCCAGCUUGCUCCUUGGUACACCGCAUAUGUGCAUCCCAGGUGGGUUUGCCCCUCAUUCAGUCACUGCUCUGUCUCCAAGGUUCCUUUCCCUCCCACCUCAGCAGCGCUCAGCUUACAAGCAGGCCCUACAGAGUUGGAUAGAGACCCACUGCCAAGCAUUACCGGCAGCCAGCAGGUUUUACAGCAACAGUGCCAAGAAGCCCAGCCUCAGGAUCUGCAAUCUCAGACAGAAUCGCUUUUGCGGCUGGCAAGGUAGGGCUAGGCAGCAGGCACAGGUGCCAUUUCACAGACUACCUCGGGCCAGCAGCUGCCCUUUAGACACCAAAUUAACUCACCAAAGUUGUCUUUCCAGCAAAGUGGUUUAAUGUGAAUUUGAAGCAUUUAGUAGCCUUGUUUUGGGUGUCUGUACCUUUCAGUGGAUGGGAUUGUCUAAGUAUGUACACAAGAAUAUUAUUGUUAAAUUCCUCAAAGAAGGUGAUAGGGGACUUUUCAAGUCCUGUAUACCAUUAGGUUAUGGAUUGUUUUGUUCAUGUACACAGCUCAUUUACUGAGUACCUCACAUGGGCCAGACACUAAUCUGCUAGGAGAGAUGAAUGGUAACAGGGACCACACUACAGAGAUCUGGACCAAAGCUCAGAGGAAGGGCUCACUGAUUCUCCCCAGCCUCCAGAACAGGAUGCCUGAAACCAUGAUGAUUGUUGCGAUAAGUCUGAGGGUGUCAUUUUAUUAUUGAUCUAUGAAUUUGGCUGUCUUGUCUUUUGAACAUUUCAUCUCGUGGUGAGUUGUUUUAAUUGGGUUUGCUCUUUGGUUGCUAAGGAAAUUUGGAGGGCCUUAGUGCAAGGUCAAGAAUCAAUGUACAACAAGGUGUGGUGGUGCACGCCUGUAGUCCUAGCUACUUGGGAGGCUGAGGCAGGAGGGUGGCUUGAGUCCAGGAGUUCUGGGCUGUAGUGUGCCAUGUCAAUUGGGUGUCAGCACUAAGUUUGGCAUCAAUAUGGGAGCAGGGGACCACUAGGUUGUUUAAGGAGGAGUGGGUGCACUGGCUCACACCAGAAAUGGAGCAGGUCAAAACUCCUGUGCUGAUCAGUAGUGGGAUCACACCUGUGAAGAGCCACUGCACUCCUGCCUAGGCAACAUAGUGAGAUCUGUCUCUUUAAGGAAAAAAAAUAGAAUAAAUGUAUAGAGACAAAUGCAGGGGGUAAGAAUCAUCGUGACCUAGAAGAUGCCAGUGUACACAAUAUUUGUAUGUGAUUUGGCACAUGUUAAUUGCAGCCUAAACCUGAACAGUGCCUUUGCCAUACCUAGAAAAAUUCCCCUUCAUGUACAAGAAACAUACAUGAAAUUAUAUUCGUAAGACAUUUGAAAUCUUGGGGGAUUGUUCUUACUAUAUGUGAAGAAGGUCUUAAUUAAAGAGAAGAGUCCUAUCUUAGGGUUUAAAACUUAUUAAAGAGGAAAGAAGAGAAAUAAGGAGGCCUGGACUCUGGUCCCAGCCACACCUCCAAUAAGCUCUGUGAUGUUAGGCAUGUCCUUUAACUUGGGUGUCAUUUCAUGCCUCUGUGACAGGGGAGUGGCCAGAUAGAUCAUCUCUAAGAUCCCUCCACCUCUACAUUCUAUGACUGCUAUUCUUACUACAUUCAUUCUAUAAGGAAGUUGGCAUAGACCCAGAAGAUAGCAAAGAAAACUAUGAAAGAUUUGGAGAAUAAGCCCUAAAAAAGCAGGUUACAAGAAUAUAAAGAGACCAAGGCAUGUGAUGGAAUCUUUAUGAAUUGAACAGCUCCUGUUAUUUCCUCUGAGAAUAGCCCAAGAGAGACCUUCAAUCGUAUCAGAAAAGAUUUAGGUUACAAAGUAGGGAUAUGAGACACCAGAGAGGUUGUAGGAUUUCCUUAUUUGGAUAUUUUUAACAAAAUAGUAGAUGACUCUCUUUCUGGGACAGUUUGAGUACCGUCUUGCCUAGAAACUAGGAGUGAACUGGAUCAACGUGUCUUAAGCUGUGUGUGGUAACAUCCCAUAAAACAGGUCUCACGUGCUGCUCUGGGAACUUCCCUGAUCUGUGCGGGGGCAGUCCAGCAGCUAGGCAGCUGAGCAGAGCGCAUCUGCCUGGGGCCAGUGAGGAGAAUGCAUCUAGACAGAGCUUUUCGUGCUGCUGAGAUCUGUUACCUAAAGCAAUAAAAAAUGGCCAGAGGAUCAGUGUCCGAUGAGGAAAUGAUGGAGCUCAGAGAAGCUUUUGCCAAAGUUGAUACUGAUGGCAAUGGAUACAUCAGCUUCAAUGAGUUGAAUGACUUGUUCAAGGCUGCUUGCUUGCCUUUGCCUGGGUAUAGAGUACGAGAAAUUACAGAAAACCUGAUGGCUACAGGUGAUCUGGACCAAGAUGGAAGGAUCAGCUUUGAUGAGUUUAUCAAGAUUUUCCAUGGCCUAAAAAGCACAGAUGUUGCCAAGACCUUUAGAAAAGCAAUCAAUAAGAAGGAAGGGAUUUGUGCAAUCGGUGGUACUUCAGAGCAGUCUAGCGUUGGCACCCAACACUCCUAUUCAGAGGAAGAAAAGUAUGCCUUUGUCAACUGGAUAAACAAAGCCCUGGAAAAUGAUCCUGAUUGUCGGCAUGUCAUCCCAAUGAACCCAAACACGAAUGAUCUCUUUAAUGCUGUUGGAGAUGGCAUUGUCCUUUGUAAAAUGAUCAACCUGUCAGUGCCAGACACAAUUGAUGAAAGAACAAUCAACAAAAAGAAGCUAACCCCUUUCACCAUUCAGGAAAAUCUGAACUUGGCUCUGAACUCUGCCUCAGCCAUCGGGUGCCAUGUGGUCAACAUAGGGGCUGAGGACCUGAAGGAGGGGAAGCCUUAUCUGGUCCUGGGACUUCUGUGGCAAGUCAUCAAGAUUGGGUUGUUUGCUGACAUUGAACUCAGCAGAAAUGAAGCUCUGAUUGCUCUUUUGAGAGAAGGUGAGAGCCUGGAGGAUUUGAUGAAACUCUCCCCUGAAGAGCUCUUGCUGAGGUGGGCUAAUUACCACCUGGAAAAUGCAGGCUGCAACAAAAUUGGCAACUUCAGUACUGACAUCAAGGACUCAAAAGCUUAUUACCACCUGCUUGAGCAGGUGGCUCCAAAAGGAGAUGAAGAAGGUGUUCCUGCUGUUGUUAUUGACAUGUCAGGACUGCGGGAGAAGGAUGACAUCCAGAGGGCAGAAUGCAUGCUGCAGCAGGCGGAGAGGCUGGGCUGCCGGCAGUUUGUCACAGCCACAGAUGUUGUCCGAGGGAACCCCAAGUUGAACUUGGCUUUUAUUGCCAACCUCUUUAACAGAUACCCUGCCCUGCACAAACCAGAGAACCAGGACAUUGACUGGGGGGCUCUUGAAGGUGAGACGAGAGAAGAGCGGACAUUUAGGAACUGGAUGAACUCCCUGGGUGUUAACCCUCGAGUCAAUCAUUUGUACAGUGACUUAUCAGAUGCCCUGGUCAUCUUCCAGCUCUAUGAAAAGAUCAAAGUUCCUGUUGACUGGAACAGAGUAAACAAACCGCCAUACCCCAAACUGGGAGGCAAUAUGAAGAAGCUUGAGAAUUGUAACUACGCGGUAGAAUUGGGGAAGAAUCAAGCGAAGUUCUCCCUGGUUGGCAUCGGUGGACAAGAUCUCAAUGAAGGAAACCGCACUCUCACACUGGCCUUGAUUUGGCAGCUAAUGAGAAGGUAUACACUGAAUAUCCUCGAAGAAAUUGGUGGUGGCCAGAAGGUCAAUGAUGACAUUAUUGUCAACUGGGUGAAUGAAACAUUGAGGGAAGCAAAGAAAAGUUCAUCCAUCUCUAGUUUCAAGGACCCGAAGAUUAGUACAAGUCUGCCUGUUCUGGACCUCAUCGAUGCCAUCCAACCAGGUUCCAUUAACUAUGACCUUCUGAAGACAGAAAAUCUGAAUGAUGAUGAGAAACUCAACAAUGCAAAAUAUGCCAUCUCUAUGGCCCGAAAAAUUGGAGCAAGAGUGUAUGCCCUGCCAGAAGACCUGGUUGAAGUGAACCCCAAAAUGGUCAUGACCGUGUUUGCCUGCCUCAUGGGGAAAGGAAUGAAGAGGGUGUGAGGCCCAAUGGGGCUGGGUGGGAGGCGGUGCACUCACUCCUGACUGCCCGGCACAGAUGCUCCAGGGAUGAUUCAAGCCAUUCCAAAGUUCAACUUGGUGACACUCUAUAAGAUUCCAAAAAGCACAUAUUAGUGCAGCCAAGUAGCCUCUCCUGUAUUUAACAAAAAGUGCUUCAUUCUUUGCAGGAGGCCCAACCUCCUAUAUAUAGGUUUCUAUUCUUGAUUUAUUUGCUUCUUCGAAAAUCUAGAGGAAAAGAAAGAAGUUAUUUUCCAGGUACCCUUCUCGCUUUUGCCAUUAGCCAAGGAUAGAAGCUGCAGUGGUAUUAAUUUUGAUAUAAUCUUUCAAACCAGCUUCAUGUGGCUUCCCUUUUCUUUGUUCAAGAUGAGGGCCAGGAGGGGAAACAUCACACCUGCCCUAAACCCUGUUCCUGGAGGUCAGCAUUUGAUCUGUUGCAAGCCCCUCUUUCUGUCCCCUCUUCCUACCCUGCCUCCCUUGACUUUGCUCCUCACACUUUUGGAACCAUGCCUUCCGGGGGGGCCCAUCUCUUCUGGCCGUCCUUGUCUCUGGGCCACUUGGAGUGUGUGAUAAAUCAGUCAAGCUGUUGAAGUCUCAGGAGUCUCUGGUAGCCUGCAGAAGUAAGCCUCAUCAUCAGAGCCUUUCCUCAAAACUGGAGUCCCAAAUGUCAUCAGGUUUUGUUUUUUUUCAGCCACUAAGAACCCCUCUGCUUUUAACUCUAGAAUUUGGGCUUGGACCAGAUCUAACAUCUUGAAUACUCUGCCCUCUAGAGCCUUCAGCCUUAAUGGAAGGUUGGAUCCAAGGAGGGUGUAAUGGAGCAUCAAGCCACUCGGCGGCAGCAUGGAGCUAUAACUAAGCAUCCUUUAGGGUUCUGCCUCUCCAGGCAUUUAGCCCUCACAUUAGAUCUAGUUACUGUGGUAUGGCUAAUACCUGUCAACAUUUGGAGGCAAUCCUACCUUGCUUUUGCUUCUAGAGCUUAGCAUAUCUGAUUGUUGUCAGGCCAUAUUAUCAAUGUUUACUUUUUUGGUACUAUAAAAGCUUUCUGCCACCCCUAAACUCCAGGGGGGACAAUAUGUGCCAAUCAAUAGCACCCCUACUCACAUACACACACACCUAGCCAGCUGUCAAGGGCAGAAUGAAUCUAUGCUGGAUAAGAAAUGGUGGAACUGCGUUAUGAAGAGCUAAUUUACUGGACAAAGAAUUCCAAAGCAAAACCAGAACAGUAUGAAUUUGAGCAGGUCUCAUAGGUUGAGCAAUUUCCCCCUAAACCAACUGAAGGCUAAAAAGCAACAGGCCAUUGUGAACCAAUGCAAGACGCCCUCUAUCAUGGUGAAAAGCUCCAUCAAUGAGGUAUCUUCUUUAGUGGUGGUAUGUAAUGGAACUUAGCCAUUUUUCAAAGCAAUUGAAAUGCAUUGCUCUGGAUCUGUUCCUUGGCAGUGGACUCAGAAAGCCAACAUGUGGCUCCUCCCAGCCCAUAACCAGUAUUUUUGCUGCUUCUGAAUACAAAUUGGUUGGUUUUGACUUCAGAUUGAACUUACUGUAGCCUCAGAUGAUUUCCCCCCUCCGCCUCCAGGAAGAAAGAAUGUUACUGCCUUAAUAAAAAAUGAAAAGAGAAUGAUGCUCAAAAUCUUUCCAAAUAAAAUGUUCCCUAUA